GUCCCCAGCCCCGUCGCCGGCGGAGGCGGGCGCGGGCGCGUCCCUGUGGCCAGUCACCCGGAGGAGUUGGUCGCACAAUUAUGAAAGACUCGGCUUCUGCUGCUAGCGCCGGAGCUGAGUUAGUUCUGAGAAGGUUUCCCUGGGCGUUCCUUGUCCGGCGGCCUCUGCUGCCGCCUCCGGAGACGCUUCCCGAUAGAUGGCUACAGGCCGCGGAGGAGGAGGAGGUGGAGUUGCUGCCCUUCCGGAGUCCGCCCCGUGAGGAGAAUGUCCCAGAAAUCCUGGAUAGAAAGCACUUUGACCAAGAGGGAAUGUGUAUAUAUUAUACCAAGUUCCAAGGACCCUCACAGAUGCCUUCCAGGAUGUCAAAUUUGUCAGCAACUCGUCAGGUGUUUUUGUGGUCGCUUGGUCAAGCAACAUGCUUGUUUUACUGCAAGUCUUGCCAUGAAAUACUCAGAUGUGAAAUUGGGUGACCAUUUUAAUCAGGCAAUAGAAGAAUGGUCUGUGGAAAAGCAUACAGAACAGAGCCCAACGGAUGCUUAUGGAGUCAUAAAUUUUCAAGGGGGUUCUCAUUCCUACAGAGCUAAGUAUGUGAGGCUAUCAUAUGACACCAAACCUGAAGUCAUUCUGCAACUUCUGCUUAAAGAAUGGCAAAUGGAGUUACCCAAACUUGUUAUCUCUGUACAUGGGGGCAUGCAGAAAUUUGAGCUUCACCCACGAAUCAAGCAGUUGCUUGGAAAAGGUCUUAUUAAAGCUGCAGUUACAACUGGAGCCUGGAUUUUAACUGGAGGAGUAAACACAGGUGUGGCAAAACAUGUUGGAGAUGCCCUCAAAGAACAUGCUUCCAGAUCAUCUCGAAAGAUUUGCACUAUCGGAAUAGCUCCAUGGGGAGUGAUUGAAAACAGAAAUGAUCUUGUUGGGAGAGAUGUGGUUGCUCCUUAUCAAACCUUAUUGAACCCCCUGAGCAAAUUGAAUGUUUUGAAUAAUCUGCAUUCCCAUUUCAUAUUGGUGGAUGAUGGCACUGUUGGAAAGUAUGGGGCGGAAGUCAGACUGAGAAGAGAACUUGAAAAAACUAUUAAUCAGCAAAGAAUUCAUGCUAGGAUUGGCCAGGGUGUCCCUGUGGUGGCACUUAUAUUUGAGGGUGGGCCAAAUGUUAUCCUCACAGUUCUUGAAUACCUUCAGGAAAGCCCCCCUGUUCCAGUAGUUGUGUGUGAAGGAACAGGCAGAGCUGCAGAUCUGCUAGCGUAUAUUCAUAAACAAACAGAAGAAGGAGGGAAUCUUCCUGAUGCAGCAGAGCCCGAUAUUAUUUCCACUAUCAAAAAAACAUUUAACUUUGGCCAGAAUGAAGCACUUCAUUUAUUUCAAACACUGAUGGAGUGCAUGAAAAGAAAGGAGCUUAUCACUGUUUUCCAUAUUGGGUCAGAUGAACAUCAAGAUAUAGAUGUAGCAAUACUUACUGCACUGCUAAAAGGUACUAAUGCAUCUGCAUUUGACCAGCUUAUCCUUACAUUGGCAUGGGAUAGAGUUGACAUUGCCAAAAAUCAUGUAUUUGUUUAUGGACAGCAGUGGCUGGUUGGAUCCUUGGAACAAGCUAUGCUUGAUGCUCUUGUAAUGGAUAGAGUUGCAUUUGUAAAACUUCUUAUUGAAAAUGGAGUAAGCAUGCAUAAAUUCCUUACCAUUCCGAGACUGGAAGAACUUUACAACACUAAACAAGGUCCAACUAAUCCAAUGCUGUUUCAUCUUGUUCGAGACGUCAAACAGGGAAAUCUUCCUCCAGGAUAUAAGAUCACUCUGAUUGAUAUAGGACUUGUUAUUGAAUAUCUCAUGGGAGGAACCUACAGAUGCACCUAUACUAGGAAACGUUUUCGAUUAAUAUAUAAUAGUCUUGGUGGAAAUAAUCGGAGGUCUGGCCGAAAUACCUCCAGCAGCACUCCUCAGUUGCGAAAGAGUCAUGAAUCUUUUGGCAAUAGGGCAGAUAAAAAGGAAAAAAUGAGGCAUAACCAUUUCAUUAAGACAGCACAGCCCUACCGACCAAAGAUUGAUACAGUUAUGGAAGAAGGAAAGAAGAAAAGAACCAAAGAUGAAAUUGUAGACAUUGAUGAUCCAGAAACCAAGCGCUUUCCUUAUCCACUUAAUGAACUUUUAAUUUGGGCUUGCCUUAUGAAGAGGCAGGUCAUGGCCCGUUUUUUAUGGCAACAUGGUGAAGAAUCAAUGGCUAAAGCAUUAGUUGCCUGUAAGAUCUAUCGUUCAAUGGCAUAUGAAGCAAAGCAGAGUGACCUGGUAGAUGAUACUUCAGAAGAACUAAAACAGUAUUCCAAUGAUUUUGGUCAGUUGGCCGUUGAAUUAUUAGAACAGUCCUUCAGACAAGAUGAAACCAUGGCUAUGAAAUUGCUCACUUAUGAACUGAAGAACUGGAGUAAUUCAACCUGCCUUAAGUUAGCAGUUUCUUCAAGACUUAGACCUUUUGUAGCUCACACCUGUACACAAAUGUUGUUAUCUGAUAUGUGGAUGGGAAGGCUGAAUAUGAGGAAAAAUUCCUGGUACAAGGUCAUACUAAGCAUUUUAGUUCCACCUGCCAUAUUGCUGUUAGAGUAUAAAACUAAGGCUGAAAUGUCCCAUAUCCCACAAUCUCAAGAUGCUCAUCAGAUGACAAUGGAUGACAGCGAAAACAACUUUCAGAACAUAACAGAAGAGAUCCCCAUGGAAGUGUUUAAAGAAGUACGGAUUUUGGAUAGUAAUGAAGGAAAGAAUGAGAUGGAGAUACAAAUGAAAUCAAAAAAGCUUCCAAUUACGCGAAAGUUUUAUGCCUUUUAUCAUGCACCAAUUGUAAAAUUCUGGUUUAACACGUUGGCAUAUUUAGGAUUUCUGAUGCUUUAUACAUUUGUGGUUCUUGUACAAAUGGAACAGUUACCUUCAGUUCAAGAAUGGAUUGUUAUUGCUUAUAUUUUUACUUAUGCCAUUGAGAAAGUCCGUGAGAUCUUUAUGUCUGAAGCUGGGAAAGUAAACCAGAAGAUUAAAGUAUGGUUUAGUGAUUACUUCAACAUCAGUGAUACAAUUGCCAUAAUUUCUUUCUUCAUUGGAUUUGGACUAAGAUUUGGAGCAAAAUGGAACUUUGCAAAUGCAUAUGAUAAUCAUGUUUUUGUGGCUGGAAGAUUAAUUUACUGUCUUAACAUAAUAUUUUGGUAUGUGCGUUUGCUAGAUUUUCUAGCUGUAAAUCAACAGGCAGGACCUUAUGUAAUGAUGAUUGGAAAAAUGGUGGCCAAUAUGUUCUACAUUGUAGUGAUUAUGGCUCUUGUAUUACUUAGUUUUGGUGUUCCCAGAAAGGCAAUACUUUAUCCUCAUGAAGCACCAUCUUGGACUCUUGCUAAAGAUAUAGUUUUUCACCCAUACUGGAUGAUUUUUGGUGAAGUUUAUGCAUACGAAAUUGAUGUGUGUGCAAAUGAUUCUGUUAUCCCUCAAAUCUGUGGUCCUGGGACGUGGUUGACUCCAUUUCUUCAAGCAGUCUACCUCUUUGUACAGUAUAUCAUUAUGGUUAAUCUUCUUAUUGCAUUUUUCAACAAUGUGUAUUUACAAGUGAAGGCAAUUUCCAAUAUUGUAUGGAAGUACCAGCGUUAUCAUUUUAUUAUGGCUUAUCAUGAGAAACCAGUUCUGCCUCCUCCACUUAUCAUUCUUAGCCAUAUAGUUUCUCUGUUUUGCUGCAUAUGUAAGAGAAGAAAGAAAGAUAAGACUUCCGAUGGACCAAAACUUUUCUUAACAGAAGAAGAUCAAAAGAAACUUCAUGAUUUUGAAGAGCAGUGUGUUGAAAUGUAUUUCAAUGAAAAAGAUGACAAAUUUCAUUCUGGGAGUGAAGAGAGAAUUCGUGUCACUUUUGAAAGAGUGGAACAGAUGUGCAUUCAGAUUAAAGAAGUUGGAGAUCGUGUCAACUACAUAAAAAGAUCAUUACAAUCAUUAGAUUCUCAAAUUGGCCAUUUGCAAGAUCUUUCAGCCCUGACGGUAGAUACAUUAAAAACACUCACUGCCCAGAAAGCGUCGGAAGCUAGCAAAGUUCAUAAUGAAAUCACACGAGAACUGAGCAUUUCCAAACACUUGGCUCAAAACCUUAUUGAUGAUGGUCCUGUAAGACCUUCUGUAUGGAAAAAGCAUGGUGUUGUAAAUACACUUAGCUCCUCUCUUCCUCAAGGUGAUCUUGAAAGUAAUAAUCCUUUUCAUUGUAAUAUUUUAAUGAAAGAUGACAAAGAUCCCCAGUGUAAUAUAUUUGGUCAAGACUUACCUGCAGUACCCCAGAGAAAAGAAUUUAAUUUUCCAGAGGCUGGUUCCUCUUCUGGUGCCUUAUUCCCAAGUGCUGUUUCCCCUCCAGAACUGCGACAGAGACUACAUGGGGUAGAACUCUUAAAAAUAUUUAAUAAAAAUCAAAAAUUAGGCAGUUCAUCUACUAGCAUACCACAUCUGUCAUCCCCACCAACCAAAUUUUUUGUUAGUACACCAUCUCAGCCAAGUUGCAAAAGCCACUUGGAAACUGGAACCAAAGAUCAAGAAACUGUUUGCUCUAAAGCUACAGAAGGAGAUAAUACAGAAUUUGGAGCAUUUGUAGGACACAGAGAUAGCAUGGAUUUACAGAGGUUUAAAGAAACAUCAAACAAGAUAAAAAUACUAUCCAAUAACAAUACUUCUGAAAACACUUUGAAACGAGUGAGUUCUCUUGCUGGAUUUACUGACUGUCACAGAACUUCCAUUCCUGUUCAUUCAAAACAAGCAGAAAAAAUCAGUAGAAGGCCAUCUACCGAAGACACUCAUGAAGUAGAUUCCAAAGCAGCUUUAAUACCGGAUUGGUUACAAGAUAGACCAUCAAACAGAGAAAUGCCAUCUGAAGAAGGAACAUUAAAUGGUCUCACUUCUCCAUUUAAGCCAGCUAUGGAUACAAAUUACUAUUAUUCAGCUGUGGAAAGAAAUAACUUGAUGAGGUUAUCACAGAGCAUUCCAUUUACACCUGUGCCUCCAAGAGGGGAGCCUGUCACAGUGUAUCGUUUGGAAGAGAGUUCACCCAACAUACUAAAUAACAGCAUGUCUUCUUGGUCACAACUAGGCCUCUGUGCCAAAAUAGAGUUUUUAAGCAAAGAGGAGAUGGGAGGAGGUUUACGAAGAGCUGUCAAAGUACAGUGUACCUGGUCAGAACAUGAUAUCCUCAAAUCAGGGCAUCUUUAUAUUAUCAAAUCUUUUCUUCCAGAGGUGGUUAAUACAUGGUCAAGUAUUUACAAAGAAGAUACAGUUCUGCAUCUCUGUCUGAGAGAAAUUCAACAACAGAGAGCAGCACAAAAGCUUACGUUUGCCUUUAAUCAAAUGAAACCCAAAUCCAUACCAUAUUCUCCAAGGUUCCUUGAAGUUUUCCUGCUGUAUUGCCAUUCAGCAGGACAGUGGUUUGCUGUGGAAGAAUGUAUGACUGGAGAAUUUAGAAAAUACAACAAUAAUAAUGGAGAUGAGAUUAUUCCAACUAAUACUCUGGAAGAGAUCAUGCUAGCCUUUAGCCACUGGACUUACGAAUAUACAAGAGGGGAGUUACUGGUACUUGAUUUGCAAGGUGUUGGUGAAAAUUUGACUGACCCAUCUGUGAUAAAAGCAGAAGAAAAGAGAUCCUGUGAUAUGGUUUUUGGCCCAGCAAAUCUAGGAGAAGAUGCAAUUAAAAACUUCAGAGCAAAACAUCACUGUAAUUCUUGCUGUAGAAAGCUUAAACUUCCAGAUCUGAAGAGGAAUGAUUAUACGCCUGAUAAAAUUAUAUUUCCUCAGGAUGAGCCUUCAGAUUUGAAUCUUCAGCCUGGAAAUUCCACCAAAGAAUCAGAAUCAACUAAUUCUGUUCGUCUGAUGUUAUAAUAUUAAUAUUACUGAAUCAUUGGUUUUGCCUGCACCUCACAGAAAUGUUACUGUGUCACUUUUCCCUCGGGAGGAAAUUGUUUGGUAAUAUAGAAAGGUGUAUGCAAGUUGAAUUUGCUGACUCCAGCACAGUUAAAAGGUCAAUAUUCUUUUGACCUGAUUAAUCAGUCAGAAAGUCCCUAUAGGAUAGAGCUGGCAGCUGAGAAAUUUUAAAGGUAAUUGAUAAUUAGUAUUUAUAACUUUUUAAAGGGCUCUUUGUAUAGCAGAGGAUCUCAUUUGACUUUGUUUUGAUGAGGGUGAUGCUCUCUCUUAUGUGGUACAAUACCAUUAACCAAAGGUAGGUGUCCAUGCAGAUUUUAUUGGCAGCUGUUUUAUUGCCAUUCAACUAGGGAAAUGAAGAAAUCACGCAGCCUUUUGGUUAAAUGGCAGUCAAAAUUUUCCUCAGUGUAUUUAGUGUGUUCAGUGAUGAUAUCACUGGUUCCCAACUAGAUGCUUGUUGGCCACGGGAAGGGAAAUGACUUGUUCUAAUUCUAGGUUCACAGAGGUAUGAGAAGCCUGAACUGAAGACCAUUUUCAAGAGGGACGGUAUUUAUGAAUCAGGGUUAGGCUCCAUAUUUAAAGAUAGAGCCAGUUUUUUUUUUUAAAUAGAACCCAAAUUGUGUAAAAAUGUUAAUUGGGUUUUUUAAACAUUGUUUUAUCAAGUCACUGUUAAGUAGAAGAAAGCCAUGGUAAACUGAUACAUAACCUAAAUUAUAAAAGCAGAAACCUAACUCACUCGUCAAGGGAAGUUACCUUUUGAGGAAAGUUAAAGUACUUUUUUCCCUAUCUGUAUCUAUAGCAACAACCCAGAACUUACAAACUUCUCCAAAGAUUUUAUUGAUUGUUAUAUCAAAUCAGAAUGUAAACAUGAACUCUUGCAUAUAUUUAAAAUUGUGUUGGAACAUUUGAACAUGAAUGCUGUUUGUGGUACUUAAGAAAUUAAUUCAGUUGGAUUAUCAUUAUGUGAUACUGGCAGAUUGCAGUGCAACCUUAUGCCAAUAAAAUGUAAUUUAACAGCCCCAGAUAUUGUUGAAUAUUCAACAAUAACAAGAAAAGCUUUUCAUCUAAGUUUUAUGCUUUAAUUUUUUUUCUUUUUUUUUCUUUUUCUUUUGUUUCCUUGGUACUAAUUUUAAUUUUUAUUUGGAAGGGAGCAGUAUAAAGCUUAUUUGUAUUUAGUAGUGUAUCUCAUAGAUACAGACAAGGCAAGAGAUGAUAAGCUGUUUAAAUAGUGUUUAAUAUUGAUUGGGGGUGGGGAGAAAGAAAAAGUGUAUUACUUAAAGAUACUAUAUACGUUUUGUAUAUCAUUAAAUCUUUAAAAGAAAUGAAAUAAAUUUAUUGUUUACAGAUGUUUAGUGAGUUUAAUCAUUCUGAAAAAUUAUCUGACAUUUUCAGGGUGUCAAUUUGAGUAUCAGUUUUUUUAAAUGAACCAUUUGUAUACCUGUGCUUUUGAUCUCCUGUCCUGUACAAUGUUUAAAUUAAUACUGAUUUCUUACUGUCUUCUUAGAAAUCUGUUUUUUGUUAGGCCAAAAAAGGGCAAUAUGGGCUGUCUGUUGAUUUUUAAUUUUAUAUUGAUUAUUUUCACAGGAUUAUAAUAGUAGCUAUACUUUUUUUUUUUUUUUUUUUUUUGAGACGGAGUCUCGCUCUGUUGCUUGGGCUGGAGUGCAGUGGUGCGAUCUCAGCUCACCACAACCGCCGCCUUCCGGGUUUAAGUGAUUCUCCUGCCUCAGCCUCCCGAGUAGCUGGGACUACAGGCACACGCCACCAUGCCCAGCUAAUUUUUAUAUUUUUAGUAGAGACAGGGUUUCACUAUGUUGGCCAGUGUGGUCACAAACUCCUGACCUUGUGAGCCACCGCACCUGGCUGCUAACACUUAUUUAGUGCCUACUGUGUACCAGACAUUACUCUAAGUAUUUCACAUAUAUUAACCUACUUAAUCCUUAUAACAAUGUUAUAAAGAAAUAGGUGUUAUUAUCCUGUUUUGCAGAUUUGAAAGUCAAGGUGCUAGAGAGGUAAAGUAACGUCCAUAAGAUUCUUACGUUUAUUUAAUAAUAAGUAGCAACGGUAGGAUUUGAACCCAGGCUGGCUGCCUUUCAUCUAUACUGUUUUUGUUUUGUUUUGUUUUGUUUUGUUUUGUUUUGUUUGUCUUGGUGGGGCAUGGUGGCUCAUGCCUGUAAUCCCAGCACUUCGGGAGGCCAAGGCAGGUGGAUCACUUGGGCUCAGGAGUUUGAGACCAGCCUGGGCAACAUGGCAAAAUCCUAUCUCUGCUAAAAAAAAAAAUACAAAAAUUAGGCCAGGUGCAGUGGCUCAUGCCUGUAAUCCCAGCACUUUGGGAGGCCAAGGUGGGCGGAUCACAAGGUCAGGAGUUCGAGACCAGCCUGACCAACAUAGUGAAACCCCGUCUCUACUAAAAAUACAAAAAAUUAGCUGGGCAUGGCGGUGAGUGCCUGUAAUCCCAGCUACUCAGGAGUCUGAGGCAGGAGAAUUGCUUGAACCUGGGAGGUGGAGGUUGCAGUGAGCUGAGAUCGUGCCAUUGCGCUCCAGCCUGGGCAACAGUGCGAGACUCCGUCAAAAAAAAAAAAAUAACUGGAUGUGAUGGUGUGCACCUGUAGUUCCAGCUACUUGGGAGACUGAGGUGGGAGGAUCACUUGAGCCUGGGAGACUGAGGCAGCAGUGAGCUGAGAUCAUGCCACUGCUUUCCAACCUGGGCAACAGAGUGAGAUCCUGUCUCAGAAAGAAAAAAAAAAAAAAGACAACCUCUUGCUCUGUUGCCCAGGCUGGAGUGUAGUAGCGUGAUCAUAGCUCACUGCAGCCGUAAACUCCUGGGCUCAAGCAAUCCUCCUGCCACUGCCUCUUGAUUAGGUGGAACCACAGGCAUGCACCACCACACGUACCUAAUUUUAUAUAUAUAUUUUUUUAUUUUUCAUUUUUAUUUAUUUUUGUUUUUUUGAGUUGAAGUCUCACUCUGUUGCCCAGGCCGGAGUACAGUGGCACAAUCUUGGCUCACUGCAACCUCUGCCUCCCAAGAUCAAGCAAUUCUCGUGCUUCAGCCUCCAAAGUAGCUGAGAUUACAGGUACCCACCAUAAUGCCUGGCUGAUUUUUGUAUUUUUCGUAGAGACAAGGUUUCACCUUGUUGGCCAGGCUGAUCUCAAACUCCUGACCUCAAGUGAUCCACCUCCCCCGGCUACCCAAAGUACUGGGAUUAUAGGUGUGAGCCACCAUGCCUGGGUAACACCCAACUAAUUUUAAAUAUAUAUUUUGUAGAGAUGGGGUCUAGCCUUGUUGCCCACGCUGGUCUCAAAUUCCUGGGCUCAAGUGAUCCUCUCGCCUGAGCUUCCCAAAGUGGUAGAAUUGCAGGCAUGAAUUGCUGCACCCAGCCUCAUCUGUGCUGUGAAUUAUGUGCUGUAUUGACUCUCAAGCAUGAUGACCAUUGGUGGUUUCUGUACCAUUUCCUGUUACUUUACUGAAACACACCUACUCCAUUAACUUCUUGGGUUAAGUCUAGAAAGUAACAGUUUACUUGUAAACCACAUUUCUUAUCCCCAAUAAGUAUUUUUUUAAGAUUAUUAAAGUUCAUUAUUACUACCCUAUGAUGUGAAAGUGUCAUUUGCUUAAUCUUUUUAAUUUUUUAUUCUCAACCUCAUCUUACUGAAGAGAAUAAAACUCUUUUACCAUAUUCUUAAAAUGUGGAAUUCUCGGCCAGGUGCAGUGGCUCACGCCUGUAAUUCCAUCACUUUGGGAGGCCAAGGUGGGUGGAUCAUCUGAGGUCAGGAGUUCAAGACCAGCCUGGCCAACAUGGUGAAACCCCGUCUCUACUAAAAAUACAAAAAUUAUCUGGGUGUGGUGGCGCGUGCCUGUAGGCCCAGCUACUCAGGAGGCUGAGGCAGGAGAAUUGCUUGAACCCAAGAGGUGGAGGUUGCAGUGAGCCUAGAUUGCUGCCACUGCACUCCAGCCUGGGUGACAGCAGAACUCUGUCUCAAAAAAAAGAUGUGGAAUUCUUUUCUGCAAAUGUUCUCUAAUAGUAUACCUUCUUCAGUCUGUCGAUAUAUGUAUGCUAUUAUUUUACAAGUAAUACAUGUUGAUUGUAUUGGAAAUUAUAGAAAAGAUUAUAUUGGAUUGUUUAGAAAAUAUUUUUAAAUGUGAAGAAAAAUAUAAAAAUUACUCCCUUGUUCCACUUUCCCCACUCUCAAGUCAGACUAUGUUGUUUUCAUAGUUAGUAGCUAGCAGUCUACCCCACUAGAUUAUAUGCUUCACAGAGGGAAGGGACCCUCAAGACUUCACUGGAUUGAGUAGCACCCAAUACCUUGCUUGCUGCCUGGUUUGUGAUGGGCAUACUGUAAGAAAAAAAAAUCUGAAUGACAAAAUGUUUUUCCAUAAUACCAGACUUCCUCUUGAAGAGAUGGGUCGUAAUGUUGUAGUCUUACAUGCUUACGUAGACAAUCAAAGCAAGAAUACUCAAUAAAUGGCUAUUUACCACUUGAAA